GUUGUUUGCUAUGAGUCUGAAUCCUGAAAGUAGAGGACUUGAUGGAGUCUGUAAUCUGUUUACCACUCAGAUGAGGAUGUAGAAUUUAUUGUUGGUGAGUUACUGAACUCUUCCUAAAGAAUGGUUGCUUAGGCAAAUUUUCUCUCAAUCAGUUUAACCCUUAGUAGUUUACAGUCUGUUCUCAGUGAAGGCCAGAGCUGUCUUUCUAAUGAUACUGUCCUUUAAGAAUCCUUGUUGGAUAUGCAUGUGUGUUGUUCAGUGGCUCAAAAUAAAGGACUGGAAUGAUGUAUGGUUCUCUCUUCAUCCAGGACAAUUUAGCUUUUGGUAACCUGGGCUGGCAUUGUUAUUAAUUUCUCUCCUAGAUCAAAUGGUUGGUGGGGUUGCUUUCCAACGUUAAGACACCACUGUGUUUGAUUAUUUUGGUUUUGUAACUAAUAGGGCAAUGAGUAAUGCAUUCAUUUUGGAAACAGGCCAGUGGUAACACAGCUCUUGGGCCUGCUGGACGUGUGGAAAAAUAGGACAGAGUAAACAAUUGAGGGCAUAAAUAAUGAAUCUUCCAACUGAGCCCUGGGAGAGUGAGGGAGAUUAUCCUCAGAGCUGUUCAGUCUGGCAGUAAAAGGGAAAGAGUCCACUGAAUUAAUUACCCAGACUGUAUUUGAUACUGCAGGAGGUAUGAGAUUGUCAAAACCAUUCAAAACAAAGUUACCUUUCCGAUACAAACUUUUAAUCCAUCUUUUUGUUUGUUUUAAACCAGACAUUUGAAUUGUUCAUUUAUUUUUUAGAGUCCAGGCCUUUGUAUCUUCUUUAAACUUUGUUCUAUAUGUUAGCAUUCUGUGAACACUUGAUGGUCCUUUUGUUUAGUCAGAUCUUAGAAGUUUACUUCAUUAGAGAUUUCAUGAUCUGUAAAUACAUAAAACGUCUCACAAAAGGUUAAGACAAGAGUUUGGGCCAGAUGUGGUGACUCAUGCUUGUAAUCCCAACACUUCAGGAGGCUGAGGCGGACGGAUCACUUGAGGCCAGGAGUUCAAGACCAGCCUGACCAACAUGGUGAAACCUCAUCUCUACUAAAAAUAUGAAAAUUAGCUGGGCAUGGUGGCACAGGCCUGUAAUUCCAGCUACUCAGGAGGCUGAGGCAGGAGAAUUGCUUGAACCCAGGAAGUGGGGGUUGCAGUGAGCUGAGAUCGUUGGACUGCACUCCAGCCUGGGUGACAGAGUGAGACUCCACAUAAAAGCAAAACAAACAAACAAAAAAACACACACACAAAAACAAGCGUUUCUUCAGCCCAAGAAUCAUUUCCAGUAUUAAGAUAAAUAUUUGCCAGGCGCGGUGGCUCACGCCUGUAAUCCCAGGACUUUGGGAAGCUGAGGCAGGCGGAUCACCUGAGUUCGGGAGUUCAAGACCAGCUUGACCAACAUGGAGAAACCCCAUCUCUAUUAAAAAUACAAAAAUUAGCUGGGUGUGGUGGUGCGUGCCUAUAAUCCCAGCUACUUGGGAAGCCCAGGCAGGAGAAUCGCUUGAACCCAGGAGGUAGAGGUUGCAGUGAGCCGAGAUUGUGCCAUUGCACUCCAGCCUGGGCAACAGGAACGAAAUUCCAUCUAAAAAAAAAAAAAGAUAAAAAAAGAUAAAUAGUCUUACUUUUGGAUAGUUUUUAUCCAGUGAAUUAAAUGAACAUCGGUCUCAGCAUUUCUCUGAAGUAGGGAAAACUAAUGGCCUGUGAUUAUCUAAAUAACUUAAGUGAUUUGGUAGUGAAGCCAGACCGAGAGCCAAGGUCUCUGAAUUCUUCCUUUCUCUGAAUUUCUAAUAUAGCUUAUUAUUUUCUCCAAGAAAUUUCAGGAACCCUAUUUGAAAUGAUUUGAAGUUUUCCUAUAUCUACCCUGAGAGGCUUUUUUUAUCUUUCUGGUUGUGAAGGGGAUCCAAACACCAGUAUGCUAUUAUUAAUCAAAAGAAGAAUGCUCAAGAUGAGGUAUUGGAGAAAGAAAAAAUAAAGUUGUUAAGAAAAGACCAACUUGAAGGUGAUUUUAUUUUGUUUUGUUUUGAGACAGGGUGCCGUCCCAAUUAUAUUGCCCAGGCUGGCCUUGAACUCCCGGACUCAAGCAGUACUCCUGACCCAGCCACCGAAGGGACUACAGGAAUAUCACAGGAGUGAUGCUGUGUUCUUCACUGCAUGAUUUCAAAAGUGUGAGCCACUGCCCCAUGUUGUGUUGAUGCCAAUCUGCCAUGCUAGCCUGUCUACCAGGGCCAGGUGACCUGUCCUUUCAGCUUCUUUCUCACACGCAGAUGAACACUGGACUUCAGAAAUGGGACACUACACAGAAAAUGAGAACUGCUCACUAUCCUACCCCAGCCGAAUUGGAUGCGUAUGCUAAGAAGGUCGCAAACAACCCACUGACUAUAAAAAUCUUCCCCAACAGUGUGAAGGUUCCCCAGCGGAAACACGUUCGUCGUACUGUGAACGGCCUCGACACAUCAGCCCAGCGCUACAGCCCCUACCCGACACAGGCUGCCACCAAGGCAGGCCUGCUUGCCAUUGUCAAAGUGCCAGCCAAAAGCAUACUCAAGGACUUUGACGGCACCCGAGCCCGGUUGCUCCCUGAGGCCAUCAUGAACCCCCCAGUGGCACCCUAUGCUACUGUGGCACCCAGCACUUUAGCCCACCCCCAGGCCCAGGCUCUGGCCCGCCAGCAGGCCCUGCAGCAUGCACAGACCCUGGCCCAUGCCCCUCCCCAGACGCUGCAGCACCCUCAGGGUAUCCCGCCACCCCAGGCACUGUCCCACCCUCAGAGCCUCCAGCAGCCUCAGGGCCUGGGCCACCCUCAGCCCAUGGCCCAAACCCAGGGCUUGGUCCACCCUCAGGCCCUGGCUCACCAGGGUCUCCAGCACCCCCACAAUCCCUUGCUGCAUGGAGGCCGGAAGAUGCCAGACUCAGAUGCCCCCCCGAAUGUGACCGUGUCUACCUCAACUAUCCCCCUUUCAAUGGCGGCCACUCUGCAGCACAGCCAGCCUCCGGACCUGAGUAGCAUCGUGCACCAGAUCAACCAGUUUUGCCAGACGAGGGCAGGCAUCAGCACUACCUCAGUGUGUGAGGGCCAGAUCGCCAACCCCAGCCCCAUUAGUCGCAGUCUGCUCAUCAAUGCAAGCACCCGGGUGUCGACCCACAGCGUCCCCACACCAAUGCCUUCAUGUGUGGUCAAUCCCAUGGAGCACACCCACGCGGCCACCGCCGCGUUGCCUGCUGCAGGUCCUGUCAACCUGCCCACAGGCAUCUCUCGCGUCCCCACUGGCUACCCUAGCGACCUCAAGCCAGUCACCUGGAACCAGCACCAGCUGGCCCACCUACAGCAGAUGUGCAGCGAGGCUAGUGGGACGCCAGCCCCUGGCCUGACAGGCAAGCAUGCGGCAGGACGCGAGUUGGCAGGGCCUGGCUUUGUGGGCAAGGCCCCUGCCUACCCGCAGGAACUCUGCCUGGCGCAGUCCUUCCAUCUGAAGCCACCCCUGGAAAAGCCGACCCCAUCCCCACCAGUCAACGGCAUGGCAGCCCCAUUGGCCUACCCCAAUGGUCACUACUUCCAACCCCUGUGGAACAACAUUCUGCCCACUCCCAAUAGCGACAGCUCGGGGUCUCAGGACCUUGCCAUGCCGUUCCACGGUGGGCAGCCCACAGGUGCACCCCUCGACUGUGCGGCAGCUCCCGGGGCCCACUACCGAGCAGGGACCGGGGGCGGUCCAGUGGCAAGCCAGAACAGCUUGAUGCAAACAGUGGAUUACCUAAGUGGGGAUUUCCAACAGGCCUGCUUCCGAGAACAGAGCCUGGCCAUGCUGAGCAAGGCCCACCGAGCCCCUGGCAACCGAGCCCCCGAUCCCACAGAGAGUCGAAGUCUUCAUAUUCAGCACCCAGGGUAUAGAUAGGUAGCCCUGCUGCCCUCCACGUGCAACACAUCAUACAUCACCCUCCUAGGUUUAGUCUUUUAAGUAACUGGAUAGUUUCAAAGUUUCACUGCUCCAGUGUGAUCAUUCUUAGAUGUCUAAGAAAGGGAAUUUGGUGGGAUCUAAGUGGGGACAGAAGGGGUCCUCUCGUCCUCCCCUCCAGCAACUUUUGGUUUUAUGUUAGAACCUAACCCUAAGCCCAGGCUUUUCUCUCCACUGACUGCCUGUCAGCUAGUCUCUCCACCUUGGCCAUUUCCAGCCAGCUCCCACCCAUCUUUUCUUGAAUCUCUUCCUGUUUCCCUUAGGACGACUGAGGUGUGGGCUGACGGAAUGCCCUAGUUGAGGUAGUAUAGGUGCUCAGGCCCCUAAUCCAGACCUCUACCUGUUGCUACCCCCCUUCCCCUCCCUCCAGGACUAAGAAGCAAGAUUUCCCAGGUGCUCUGAAAGCUAAUUACUUACUCAUCGAAGGAUCUCAAAUCAAAGCUGACCCAGUCUUCAUAUCCUUCAAGUUCCUUUCCAUUCCUCAAGGCUUUGUUUUGUGUCUAUAUUGAUCCCACAGCCACUGCACUUGCCCUUGCCACACUUGAUCUCAAGGGCAUCUUGGAAGUAUUUGACCAUUUCUUGAGAUAUGGGGGGAAAAAGUCUUUGUAUUGGCAUCUUGGUUCCAGACUCCCCUUUCCAAACCUAGAAAAAUACAGUGACCUUUGAGCAUACCCAAGAUCCCUUUCUCACUGUUGCCUGUCCCCUAACUCACCUCCCCACAGCCCCUAUCCUUUCCCCCUCAACAAAAACAAAAUCUACCUUACUUGAGGAAUUAGGUAGGUAAGGAAUGAUCACAUUGGAGUUUGGGAUUAAAAACACCAAAAAAAAAAAAAUGCAUUUGGUUCUCUCUACACUGGCUAAGAAUAUUGCUCUACACUGUAAGUUUUAAACGUUACGUUUCUGUAUGAAUGUAGUGUGGGUUUGAGUAGCAUUGUGUGUGAGUGGCCCCACAGGUACAUUCACCCUCUAGUGCAGCCCCUCAGUUUAAUGAAGGAAAAAAAAACAAACACAAAGCCUUAAGCUCUUUGAGUACUUCCUUUACCAAAUGAGCAUGGUUCUAACACCUGGAGCUGGGCCUACAUUGGAAACAAGCCCCUCCUGCCCUCUGUCCAUUCUUAGAGCAUACCUUCAUCCACUCCAUGCUCAGCACGUCUCAUCCCAAGCGACAAUUAGUUGGCUAGAAACACUUUUCUGUAAUUUUAAACUUAGACUGUUUUGUUACAAAUUUUUGCACCAUUCUGUUAAAGAUGCAGAAUUGGGCUUUUUUAUUUUUUACAGAUGAAAUAAGCCCUUACCUUUCCUCUUGUCUCUGGGGAAUGUCAGCUGAUGGUUCUUAUUUAAGGUUUUGCAUUUUGUUCACUAUCCACUACUGUUCGUUAGCCAGAAAUUCUCUAGUGAUCUGAAGCAAUGUGACUGAAGACCAGUUUUAAGUUAUGUGUUGGCAAGUUGCCUUAUAUUUAAAAGGAAAAAGAAAAAAAAAAAAGCCUGAUUGUGUUAUGCCAAAUGAUAGCAACAUGAAGUCCUAAUUUAUUGUUCCCAAUUGUUUUCCUGCCGUCUGUGAACACUGGUACCUCCCUGUCCUGAUCCCCCAGGAGCACCUGUAGCUUCUGACUCAAUGCCUUCUCCGAAGGUGUUGGCCGCCAUCUCACCCAGGGCCCUCUUCCAGUUCCUGCUUUUCUGAGUCAGAUUUAAAGAGCACCACUGUCUUCCCCCUACCCCUUGCUUGAUCUCCAAAGCAGAUAUUCUUGCUGUAUUUUUUUUUCCUCCCCAAUACCUCUCCCUGAAAGGUGAGCUGCUAUUUUAGGAAACUGGACCAGACACCAACUUGGGGGCUUUAAGUCAAACAACCUCAAACCCAUCUCUUCCUGUGUAGGGGUGCAAGCCUCUGAAGCUCUCACUCCCACCCUUAGUCUGCAUGGAAAAUGUACUGUGAUCCCCCUGCCCCCAACUGCCCUCGCCUUUGGUGUGAGAUGUUCCUUCUUUCGGAGUUCAGCCUGAGUCCCUCUCCCCUCUGCCAGCCAACCCCCAGCCAGCAAUAAGGGUCCAAGCCAGGGCCUCCUCUCCACACUCCCUGUCUCCAUCCUACACUACCCUAGGGAAUACCUGGAUUCCCCAUUCUAUCCACAUACUGUAGCAUUCAUUCUCCAUCUCUCUCACCUCACCUGUGGUGGUUUAUGGGUGUGAUGGGGUUUUUAAGAUUAUUAUAAACCAGUAAAAAUAAGAAAACCUC